AGUGCCUCAUGUUUAAUAAGUACUUGUACAUAUUGAUAGACUGCAUGAAGUAUGCAUAAACAUACUUAGAAAAACCUGGACUGAAAGACAAACCCUACACUGUGGUUUCUUCACCCACUGCCCUAACUCACUGUGCUGUACAGGGGGACUGAAUAAAAUCAUUUCACAUGCAUUUCCUGCACCCCCUUGCUCUGACCUGGCCCCAUUUUGGAUGGAUCCAGUGACUCUUCCCUUCCCCACCAUGCAAAACAGAAAAACACAUCUUUCUGUUUUGAUCCAGUACUGCCCACACGUUGGGGAAAAUGUUAAUAUACUAUUUGUAUGAAUAUAUUUAAUCAAAGGGCAUGAUGUUGAUACAGUAAAAUUGGCCUGUGGUCUGGUGGCUUCCUGGGCAGAUGAUAGCAGGAGGGUUUUGCGACAGAAUAGCCUUGGAGUCAGGACUUUUGUAAGAAGAUUAGGUCAGUGUUUGAUUUGAUGUUUCAUUCUGCAAAGUCACCUACAGAGAAAUCAAACAUUUACAUGUUUAUUAACUGGUGCUUUUGGUUUUGGCAUGUGGCCACAGGCUUUGGGCUGGAUGAGCUCUGGGAAUGCACAAAAAUCUCUCAUUCCUUCUCUUGUAUGGGUAGAUAAGCAGGAAAAUAUUUACCUUUUCAGGUUAUCCUCUUCAAAGAAGCCUGAAACUUCUUCAGCCACAUCAUCUUCCUGCCAGAGUCUGAAAACCAACAGGCUUUCAAGAGACCAAGGGUUGAGUGGAGUCAUUUAGGGAAUGACAUGUAUCCAGGAAUAACUCAAGUCACCUGUACUGGAAAUCAGUUUGCUGAAAUUAAUCAACGAUUCUUGAAGUUGAAGAAAAGUUGUUCUCUCUACAGGAGGUUCCAGCCUUGGCAAGAGGAGUGUGGCCCUUCCUGGAAUCCCUCUGGACACACCCUCCUAGCAUCCUCUAGGAAAGAUGCGGCAGCUCAAAGGGAAGCCCAAGAAGGAGACCUCCAAGGACAAGAAGGAGCGGAAGCAAGCCAUGCAGGAGGCCCGGCAGCAGAUCACUACAGUGGUGCUGCCCACGCUGGCCGUGGUCGUGCUCUUGAUCGUGGUGUUUGUGUACGUGGCCACGCGCCCCACCAUCACCGAGUGAGCCCCGCAGCCGGCUGCGGACCCCAUCGGCAGGGAGAGGAGGCGCGGGAGGGGGACGCAAACAAAAAAUGGCUUUCAUAUUCAGAGAUGUUCAUGUUGCUGAGCUGUAAGCAGGAGCACCCUGUCUUCUCUGGUCUUUGACUUGAUUAAAGUAUCUCCGCUUUCUUGGGAGGGAAUAGGGGAUGUUUUAUCAGUGAAUGUGCCAUACACCUUAUGGUCCACUUCAUGUGCCUUUCAGACUUCAAAGCGCGCGCGCAUGUGUGUGUGUGUGUGUGUGUGUGUGUGUGUGUGUGUGUGCUUCUUUUUCUCUCCUAAAAAUCGAUAAGUAGCUCCACCUGAAGAGGGAUGGAACCUCUGGGUCAGGAAACAGCUGGAAUCCACACUCACCUCAUUCCCAUUGUUUGGAUCAUGCUUCUUUCCAACACGUGUUCACAAUCUCCAAAGGGACUGUAUUUCUUCUCUGUGCUUAAUGUGAUUUGAAAUAUGUUGAAUCAAAGUGAAAUAUUUAUUUUUUGAAUAAAGGAGAUAAUAGCCUUAAA